AGACUCCUCCCCCUCACCGUCCCAAUUGUAUUCCCUGGAAGAGCAGCCGGAAAAGCCUCCGCCUGCUCAUACCAGGAUAGGCAAGAAGCUGGUUUCUCCUCGCAGCCGGCUCCCUGAGGCCCAGGAACCACCGCGGCGGCCGGCACCACCUGGACCCAGCUCCAGGCGGGCGCGGCUUCAGCACCACGGACAGCGCCCCACCCGCGGCCCUCCCCCCGGCGGCGCGCUCCAGCCGGUGUAGGCGAGGCAGCGAGCUAUGCCCGCGGCAUGGCCCGGCGCUGCGGCCCCGUGGCGCUGCUCCUUGGCUUCGGCCUCCUCCGGCUGUGCUCAGGGGUGUGGGGUACGGAUACAGAGGAGCGGCUGGUGGAGCAUCUCCUGGAUCCUUCCCGCUACAACAAGCUUAUCCGCCCAGCCACCAAUGGCUCUGAGCUGGUGACAGUACAGCUUAUGGUGUCACUGGCCCAGCUCAUCAGUGUGCAUGAGCGGGAGCAGAUCAUGACCACCAAUGUCUGGCUGACCCAGGAGUGGGAAGAUUAUCGCCUCACCUGGAAGCCUGAAGAGUUUGACAACAUGAAGAAAGUUCGGCUCCCUUCCAAACACAUCUGGCUCCCAGAUGUGGUCCUGUACAACAAUGCUGACGGCAUGUACGAGGUGUCCUUCUAUUCCAAUGCCGUGGUCUCCUAUGAUGGCAGCAUCUUCUGGCUGCCGCCUGCCAUCUACAAGAGCGCAUGCAAGAUUGAAGUAAAGCACUUCCCAUUUGACCAGCAGAACUGCACCAUGAAGUUCCGUUCGUGGACCUACGACCGCACAGAGAUCGACUUGGUGCUGAAGAGUGAGGUGGCCAGCCUGGACGACUUCACACCUAGUGGUGAGUGGGACAUCGUGGCGCUGCCGGGCCGGCGCAACGAGAACCCCGACGACUCUACGUACGUGGACAUCACGUAUGACUUCAUCAUUCGCCGCAAGCCGCUCUUCUACACCAUCAACCUCAUCAUCCCCUGUGUGCUCAUCACCUCGCUAGCCAUCCUUGUCUUCUACCUGCCAUCCGACUGUGGCGAGAAGAUGACGUUGUGCAUCUCAGUGCUGCUGGCGCUCACGGUCUUCCUGCUGCUCAUCUCCAAGAUCGUGCCUCCCACCUCCCUCGACGUGCCGCUCGUCGGCAAGUACCUCAUGUUCACCAUGGUGCUUGUCACCUUCUCCAUCGUCACCAGCGUGUGCGUGCUCAACGUGCACCACCGCUCGCCCACCACGCACACCAUGGCGCCCUGGGUGAAGGUCGUCUUCCUGGAGAAGCUGCCCGCGCUGCUCUUCAUGCAGCAGCCACGCCAUCAUUGCGCCCGUCAGCGCCUGCGCCUGCGGCGACGCCAGCGUGAGCGCGAGGGCGCUGGAGCCCUCUUCUUCCGCGAAGCCCCAGGGGCCGACUCCUGCACGUGCUUCGUCAACCGCGCGUCGGUGCAGGGGUUGGCCGGGGCCUUCGGGGCUGAGCCUGCACCAGUGGCGGGCCCCGGGCGCUCAGGGGAGCCGUGUGGCUGUGGCCUCCGGGAGGCGGUGGACGGCGUGCGCUUCAUCGCAGACCACAUGCGGAGCGAGGACGAUGACCAGAGCGUGAGUGAGGACUGGAAGUACGUCGCCAUGGUGAUCGACCGCCUCUUCCUCUGGAUCUUUGUCUUUGUCUGUGUCUUUGGCACCAUCGGCAUGUUCCUGCAGCCUCUCUUCCAGAACUACACCACCACCACCUUCCUCCACUCAGACCACUCAGCCCCCAGCUCCAAGUGAGGCCCUUCCUCAUCUCCAUGCUCUUUCACCCUGCCACCCUCUGCUGCACAGUAGUGUUGGGUGGAGGAUGGACGAGUGAGCUACCAGGAAGAGGGGCGCUGCCCCCACAGAUCCAUCCUUUUGCUUCAUCUGGAGUCCCUCCUCCCCCACGCCUCCAUCCACACACAGCAGCUCCAACCUGGAGGCUGGACCAACUGCUUUGUUUUGGCUGCUCUCCAUCUCUUGUACCAGCCCAGGCAAUAGUGUUGAGGAGGGGAGCAAGGCUGCUAAGUGGAAGACAGAGAUGGCAGAGCCAUCCACCCUGAGGAGUGAUGGGCAAGGGGCCAGGAAGGGGACAGGAUUGUCUGCUGCCUCCAAGUCAUGGGAGAAGAGGGGUAUAGGACAAGGGGUGGAAGGGCAGGAGCUCACACCGCACCGGGCUGGCCUGACACAAUGGUAGCUCUGAAGGGAGGGGAAGAGAGAGGCCUGGGUGUGACCUGACACCUGCCGCUGCUUGAGUGGACAGCAGCUGGACUGGGUGGGCCCCACAGUGGUCAGCGAUUCCUGCCAAGUAGGGUUUAGCCGGGCCCCAUGGUCACAGACCCCUGGGGGAGGCUUCCAGCUCAGUCCCACAGCCCCUUGCUUCUAAGGGAUCCAGAGACCUGCUCCAGAUCCUCUUUCCCCACUGAAGAAUUCUGCACCCUCUGGACUUCCCUCUUCUUCCUUCCUUUCUCAGGCUCAAGGUGUGGGGGGCAAGGCUGAGUAUUAGGGGAGCUUCUGAGUUCUGAAUCUUUGGGUGACCUGCUUGGAGUCUCAGGUCCAAAUACUUGAAAUCUGUGAGAAGUCCAAGUUCAUGGGCUUUUGGAACUGGAAGAACUUUGUACAGCCAUGGAUUCCAACAUAAGCCAUGUUGCAGAUGAAGAAACUGACCCACACGGUGAGACAAGCACAGGUGGGUCUGACUCUUCCUCCCUGCCCUGAGAUCCAUCUGUCGAGUGCCCUGUUUUUUCCCCACUUUGAACUGACUGGUUACUCUAAGGAAGUGAACUGAGGAUGUUAGCUUUAAGCCAACCCAGCCUCUUUGUCCACAGCAGAGCUGAGGUGAACAGCUGGAACCCUGCUACAUCCGUGCUGCUCCAGUCUGUUCUGCUCAUGGCUCCAUCCUUCUGGCUGUCACUCUUCCUCUUCCCCUUCCCAACCAAACCUGAGCAGCUUUGAAGCAGAACUUGGGAAGGACAGGGCUGCUGCUGCCAGCGACACCUCAGAAAGCAUAGCCUCGGCUUCCUGCCCCAUGUGUCCCUGGAAGCUGUACCCUGACUCUGCUUCCAGAGGCCAGCAGAUGGUGGGUUACAGACGGGUCAGCCUGCCAAGUGCACCUGAGGGACCUGACCUGACACAAGCCAUUUUGUCCCUAGAGCCCAGCUGGGACUCCUGCUUCUCUAGGCAGGGCAGAGGGAGGAGACACAGCACAGGCACAGAGCAUGGGACAGGGACCCCCGAGUCUGGAUUCAAGUCCUGGCCCUGCUAGUAACUCAUGUGAGCCAGCUUGAGCAAGUCCCUUCAUCUUGCUAGAGCUCAGCUUCCUUGCCUAUAAAACGUAGGUGGCAAUGCCCUCUUCCUGAGGUUGCUGGGAGGAUAAGGCAGUGCUUGUGAAAAAGUCUAGCGCUGUACCUGGCACAGAGUAGAUGCUUCAUGAAUGUUGAGUCUGACAGGCAACUGGAGCUGGUGAGAAUGGGGUCCCCUGACUGUCAUGCCAGCCUCCCUCCCAGGCCCACUCUUCCCCCCUCUUCCCUGAGGAAACCAAGUCUCCCUUAUCAGGAAGAGCUGGGGGAGCUGGGAGGAACAUUACAGGAACACCAGAGGGAGUCUAGCGGGUGGGCAGGCUUCUCUCUGCAGCCCCCUCAGCAGUUUCAUUCCAUUCCUGGGCUGAACCCUUGCCCUGGCCCUGCCUCCCUUCUGGGUCAGCACCUCCUGACACAGGUGUGUGCUCAGGGACCCCAGGCUCUAGUCCUGUACUGGCUGUGGAAGCCUAUCACUGGGACAGGAAGCCAGUGGCUGCAGGAGACAGGCCUCAGCGCAUCUCGUCUGUCAGGAUGGGCUCACGGACACCUUUUCUUGGUAGCAGGGAGUGUCUCUGCACUAUGGAAACUUUCCCUCUUCUAGAGCGGAUUGGGAGUUGCCUGUAUUAUGCCUGAACCCUCCUUGAACUCAUGGUCCUGGGGAAGGCGUCUUGGAACCAGAAACAGCAACAGGAAAGGAGCCUCCCUCUGAAGGGUAGGAUGCCGGCCUGAGGCCCUCCCUCUUGGCUCUCCCAGGGCCUGGGCUACCCCGAGGCCCCAGCAGCUGCUGCUGUGGCUGUACUUGCUUUUAAUAUUUCCCAUACAUGGCUGUUGUCCAAGUUAAGUCACCAAAUGGUGCUAGAGGGGAUGGCAGAGAGCAGCUUGUCCAGCUCCUCUCCAUGACCCGGUUAACACACGAGUAAACAGGCCUAGAGCUUGUCUGCUGUUUGACCUCUUUUAAGACCCGGCUGUGCUGCAUCUACAAAAUGAAGAUGACAGAGCUAGCCGAGGUCUUCAGCAAGGAAGAAAGGGGUCAGUGUAUAUGAAAGGGUUACCUGGGCAGUGUCAUUCCCUCCAUCUCUGUACGCAGCCCUUUGGGAACCAUCACAAUAAGGAAGAGGUGAGGGCAGAGGUGAAGGAUCCACUGCCCAGGCAAGGUGCUACCAUGUGGUGGGAGAGUGUGAACCCUCAAGUGCACUGGGAAGCUUUGGGGAACCACAGUCUCUUCCACCCUUGGGUCGUGUGUCGUCCUCUUCUCUUGAUGUCAGGGAAGCCCCUAUGCCUCCUUCCCGUGGUGGGGCUAUCUCUGCAGAGAAUCGGGUGCCCAGCUUAAUGCUGGGCAAGGACUGGAGGAAGCUCCAGAUCUGGAGGUGGCAGAGAUACUGGAUGGAAACCUGGAGCAAGGGUUUGGGAGGGGAAGUGAGGAAACAGGUUGAGACUAUCUCCAUCAGAGAUGGCAAGGCCACAGGUGAUCUGAGAACUAUUUUUGUCUGAAAAGAAGGCAUGCACAGGCUCUCUGCUUUUGACAGGUGGCGUUGCAGUGGGAGGAAGGCAGCUUCCUGGCGGGGAGAUAGAAAUACUAGAACAGCUGGUACCAAGUUAUUGAAAAUUUAAAAGCAAACAAGACACAGCAGCCCCCAGGUGGUGUGUUCUACUGAGGAAGGCUACGGCAGAGGAAGGGCAAGACCGUUUCCCCCAAUGGUCUUGAAACGGAAGAGGAAACAGGGAGGGCUCUUUGGAUGGUUUGGGGACCUGGGGCUGUUUGUAUCCCAGUAUUAGCUCCUGUUACUAAGGGUCUGCUCUGCGCCAGGUCCUCAGCAUGCGUUGUCUUUAUUCCGCGUGACAAUCCUAUGGGAAGGGGCCUCCACCUACGUAACAGAAAUGCGGCUCAGAAAGACCAAGUGACAGCUAGUGAGUAGUGCUGGGCCUGAACCCCAAAGUCCACACUCUUGCUAUAGCCGCUGAGGCAGGCAGAAGAGCUCCUUGGGAGGAAAGUAAGGGGCAUUCAAAGCCUUCUCUGAAUCACUCCCCAAGCCAGAGUAGACCUGGUUCCAGUUGUCCCCCCCUUGUUUCCGGGCAGAGUCAGGCAGGUGUCAUACCAUCCCUCCCCGCCCAACCAGUGCUGGCCAGACUCCCAUUCACCGACCUUGACUAGACAGCGAACAGCCACCUUUUAGUAUUCAUCCCAACAGGUCCAGGCGGUCAGUGUGAUAGCCACGCAGUUCCUAAGGGACUGUAGGUCUAGGAAUCAUUAGGACACUCACUCAGCCACCCUCGAUGCCCCCAUCUUCCCCACACUGCCCUUGGCCUCCCCGCUCUGCACGCCUGGAGUAUUUGCACUGGUCUAGCCUACUCCAGGUCAGACUCAUUAGGAACUCAAGAUUCUCGUAAAGAAAGUUGUUUCCAAAGUUGUCUUGUCACUCUAUUUGGGGGUUGGGAGAGAGCCCGUGGGGGCCAGCGUUGGCGAAUACAGGAAAAAGGGAGAAUGCUGGAGAAACUGGACUCGUGAGAGCUUAAAGACAUCACAAGAAUCCAAAGAAAAA